GACAGUGCAUGGGCAGGACAGGCAACGAGAGGCAGCUCUCUGCGGCACUCGUGUCCUGGCCUCGGCACCUGGGCAUGUGUGGCGUGCAUGGGAGUGAGACCCAGACAGCUGCAGCAAUGUGUCCUCUGCCACCCACUGCUGCUGGUGUCUGUGUUGGGGAGCGAUGGUCCAGGAGCACAUUAGGGCCCUCAGUGUACUGUCUCUUUGUGUCGGCGUUGACACUCCGGUCUUCAGCUGGCGGAGCAUGAAACGGUUUCACAGUACUUUCAAGACUUGAUACAGAUGGAUGCUCUUGUCUCCACGUGUCAGCCCCACCAAGUCCAGUCAGCCUCAGGUUCAGUGUGGACUGGGUCACGCUGUUUAGUCAGAUCCUCACCCCUCCUCUCUCAAGUGACAUUCCCUUCUCCACUGGAGUUGGAGGGGACGAGGCAUAGCAGGGCCCUGCCUGGUGUGUCUGCCUCUGCCUCUGUGCUCUGCCCUCCCACCCUGGCACCUGCCUGUUCCCCUCCUCUCUCUCGGUGAGCUGGGAUCCUGACAGACCCAGGCCCCCUUCCCAUCACCCUGUGUGGCAGCCCGCGCCCCAGCACCCCUUCGCAGUCCGAUGAGAAGGCACCUUCCUUAAGACCAAUGUCAGGCUCUCCCUCUGCCUGAGGGACUGGCUGAGUUGUUCUGGUUCUGAGAUGGCUUUGGGGGACUGAGUUGCUUAGUGGGUCUGGGGUCGGAGUGGUUGUGAUGACAUGGACAGCCCCUCUUCCCAGAAAGGUGCUGGCGUCUCUGGAUUAGAAAUCAUGGGGGGAGGCAAAGCCGGGGCUGGGAGAGGGCAACCAGGCUUGUUCCUGGCACCCACUGGGAAAGCAACCUGGCAGCAGCUCACGGGGGAAGAAGCAGCCACCGUUCUCCAGUGUUCCUCACAAAGACUGAGUCCUUCUCAGCAGACACACCCAGGGCCCCUGCCAGGUUCUCCCUUCAGGGCGACAGAUGUGGACAGAUGGUUCCCUUACGAUGUACAGACCACAGCAGAGGUAUACAGACCGCUCCUUCAGCACAAUUAUGUGCUGAUACAAAGAGUUACAGGAAUAGUGACCCUUUAAGGAUAGGAACGUGAUGGAUAAUUUAAACUUUUUAAAAUUCUUGGCCGGGCGCAGUGGCUCACGCCUAUAAUCUCAGCCCUGUGGGCGGCUGAGGUGGGCGGAUCAUGAGGUCAGGAGAUCGAGACCAUCCUGGCCAACAGGGUGAAACCCCGUCUCAACUCUACUAAAAAUAUAAAAAUUAGCUGGGCGUGGUGGCGCACACUUGUAAUCUCAGCUACUUGGGAGGCUGAGGCAGGAGAAUCGCUUAAACCCGGGAGGCAGAGGUUGCAGUCAGCCGAGAUCGCGCCAUGGCACUCCAGCCUGGCAACAGAGCAAGACUCCAUCUCAAAAAAAAAAAAUUAUUUUGGCUAUUUUUCACAUGUAUUAUUGUGUAGUUUUACUACUCAUGUUUUCAAGCAUCCCUCCAACAAAACAGCAGAGAUAACCAUUUGUGGCUAGGAAAUGGGAAUUUACAGAAGAGAUGGCAUUUGACUUGGAUCUUGAGGAGUGUGUGGGAGUUUAUCAUGUAGACACAGUAGAAGUGUCACAGACAAAAAAUAGCUCAGACAUUAAAAUUAUUUUUUUAUUAUUUAUUUAUUGAGACGGAGUCUCUCUGUCGCCCAGGCUGGAGUGCAGUGGUACGAUCUUGGCUCACUGCAACCUCCGCCUCCCGGGUUCACGCCAUUCUCCUGCCUCAGCCUCCCGAGUAGCUGGGACUGCAGGUGCCCGCCACCACGCCCGGCUAAUUUUUAUAUUUUUUAGUAGAGAUGGGGUUUCACCAUAUUGGCCAGGCUGGUCUCGAACUCCUGACCUCAGGUGAUCCGCCUGCCUUGGCCUCCCAAAGUGCUGGGAUUACAGACGUGAGCCACCGGGCCCAGCCGCAGACAUUAAAAUUAAAGGGCAUCCGGACAUGGUGGCUGGUGCUUGUCAUCCCAGCUACUCAGGAGGCUGAGGUGGGAGGGUCACUUGAGCCCAGGAGUUCAAAAUUAAAAUGAGCCAUGGUCACACCACUGCACUCCAGCCUGGGCAACAGAGCAAGACCCAGUCUCUUAAAAACAAAAAACAAGAAGAACCCCAGAGUAUGUCUAGGGAAGGGCAAACACUUGGCUUGGCUGGGACAUAGAGACAUUUGAAGGGAAUGCUAAGAGAGAGAGGUGGGGAACUAGGUGAGGAGUGCAGCCCAGAGGGCGUGCGUGCCAGCCAGGAUUGGGCCCUCGAGGACUGAGGGAAGGGCCCAUAGUAACAGCAGGCAGCCAGGUGCCGUGGUGGACUCUUCAUGACAGUUUUAUGAUGGGGAUUCCAUUUUUCCCCUCUUUACAGAUGAGGAAAUUGAGGCUUAGAGGUUGUUUGCUCAAAAGUUGCCCAGCUGGAGCGUGAUGGAGUCAGGAUUUCAGCCCCCAUCUGCCUGACUCCUGAUCUCAUUGUCACCGUUGGGAGGAAGUCUGAGGCGGUUGAAGCAGCCCGACCGCCUCCUCCCCAGACCAGUGUGAUGUCAGGCCCAGCCGACCUGAAGGUGCAGGGUUGCCUGGUGCAGGUUCCUCUGGGAUGAGGUUCUGAGGGCACCCAGCCUGGCCUUGCUCCAGAAGCCUGGGCUCUGCGCACAGAGGGGGAAGGUGCCCUGAGCUCAGCCCUAAAUACCUGGUACUAAAGAGUCAGUGGCUGCUUCAGAUGCCACCAGAAUGAGAAGCGGUGCCUUGGGGCCCCGGGGGAGAGGAAGAGCCUCUGCCCUGGGACUUCCUGUGCCGGCGAUGGCCUCGCGCCAGUGCUGGGCGCGGCACCCCCGCGUGGGCCUGUGUUGGGCGGCUUUUGAGCAGGAGUCCGGGCCCUCGUGUCACCGCUCUGAAGUCAAGGAGCUGGAUUACUGGGCCAGUUACAGGUCUUGUUCUUACUGGACAUCCAAGACCGGCCAGCUGUGGAAACCCAGCGGGGCUUGCAGCAGAGCGGAGGGGCCCACCCCGUUCUUCCUCAUUUCCCACCCCUGGUGUGGGAUUUGGGGGGCUCCUGGGCAGAGUGCGAAGCUCCGGAGCCGAGGCCACUGGAUCCCCAGUGACUGCUCGGGGGGGUCCCGCUGCGUGGAGAUGCCGGCAGCACGUCGGUUCCCUGGCCUGGAGCUCUCCUUCCCUCUCCUGGCCAGACUGCGGCGACGCCUGUACACAAGGCUGGGAGGCGGCAGAAUGCAGCCAGAGGAGGGCACAGGCUGGCUGCUGGAGCUGCUGUCCGAGGUGCAGCUGCAACAGUACUUCCUGCGGCUCCGAGAUGACCUCAACGUCACCCGCCUGUCCCACUUUGAGUACGUCAAGAAUGAGGACCUGGAGAAGAUCGGCAUGGGUCGGCCUGGCCAGCGGCGGCUGUGGGAGGCUGUGAAGAGGAGGAAGGCCUUGUGCAAACGCAAGUCGUGGAUGAGUAAGGUGUUCAGUGGAAAGCGACUGGAGGCUGAGUUCCCACCUCAUCACUCUCAGAGCACCUUCCGGAAGACCUCGCCCGCCCCUGGGGGCCCAGCAGGGGAGGGGCCCCUGCAGAGCCUCACCUGCCUCAUUGGGGAGAAGGACCUGCGCCUCCUGGAGAAGCUGGGUGAUGGUUCCUUUGGCGUGGUGCGCAGGGGCGAGUGGGACGCGCCCUCAGGGAAGACGGUGAGUGUGGCUGUGAAGUGCCUGAAGCCCGAUGUCCUGAGCCAGCCAGAAGCCAUGGACGACUUCAUCCGGGAGGUCAAUGCCAUGCACUCGCUCGACCACCGAAACCUCAUCCGCCUCUACGGGGUGGUGCUCACGCCGCCCAUGAAGAUGGUGACAGAGCUGGCACCUCUGGGAUCGUUGUUGGACCGGCUACGUAAGCACCAGGGCCACUUCCUCCUGGGGACUCUGAGCCGCUACGCUGUGCAGGUGGCUGAGGGCAUGGGCUACCUGGAGUCCAAGCGCUUUAUUCACCGUGACCUGGCUGCCCGCAAUCUGCUGUUGGCUACCCGCGACCUGGUCAAGAUCGGGGACUUUGGGCUGAUGCGAGCACUACCUCAGAAUGACGACCAUUACGUCAUGCAGGAACAUCGCAAGGUGCCCUUCGCCUGGUGUGCCCCCGAGAGCCUGAAGACACGCACCUUCUCCCAUGCCAGCGACACCUGGAUGUUCGGGGUGACACUGUGGGAAAUGUUCACCUACGGCCAGGAGCCCUGGAUCGGCCUCAACGGCAGUCAGAUCCUGCAUAAGAUCGACAAGGAGGGGGAGCGGCUGCCCCGGCCCGAGGACUGUCCCCAGGACAUCUACAACGUCAUGGUCCAGUGCUGGGCUCACAAGCCAGAGGACAGACCCACGUUUGUGGCCCUGCGGGACUUCCUGCUGGAGGCCCAGCCCACAGACAUGCGGGCCCUUCAGGACUUUGAGGAACCGGACAAGCUGCACAUCCAGAUGAAUGAUGUCAUCACCGUCAUCGAGGGAAGGGCCGAGAACUACUGGUGGCGUGGCCAGAACACACGGACGCUGUGUGUGGGGCCCUUCCCUCGCAACGUGGUGACCUCCGUGGCCGGCCUGUCGGCCCAGGACAUCAGCCAGCCCCUGCAGAACAGCUUCAUCCACACAGGGCAUGGCGACAGUGACCCCCGCCACUGCUGGGGCUUCCCGGACAGGAUUGACGAACUGUAUCUGGGAAACCCCAUGGACCCCCCCGACCUCCUGAGCGUGGAACUGAGCACCUCCCGGCCCCCCCAGCAUCUAGGAGGGGUGAAAAGGGAGCCUCCACCUCGCCCACCUCAGCCUGCCUUCUUCACUCAGAAACCAACCUAUGACCCUGUGAGCGAGGACCAAGACCCCUUGUCCAGCGACUUCAAGAGGCUGGGCCUGCGGAAGCCAGGCCUGCCCCGAGGGCUGUGGCUGGCGAAGCCCUCGGCGCGGGUGCCGGGCACCAAGGCCAGCCGAGGCAGCGGGGCUGAGGUCACGCUCAUCGACUUCGGUGAGGAGCCCGUGGUCCCGGCCCUACGGCCCUGCGCGCCCUCCCUGGCGCAGCUGGCCAUGGACGCCUGCUCCCUGCUGGACGAGACCCCGCCUCAGAGCCCCACGCGGGCACUGCCCCGGCCCCUGCACCCCACGCCUGUGGUGGACUGGGACGCACGCCCGCUGCCCCCCCCGCCCGCCUAUGACGACGUGGCCCAGGAUGAGGAUGACUUUGAGAUCUGCUCCAUCAACAGCACCCUCGUGGGCGCGGGGGUCCCUGCCGGGCCCAGCCAGGGCCAGACCAACUACGCCUUUGUGCCUGAGCAGGCGCGGCCGCCCCCUCCCCUGGAGGACAACCUGUUCCUCCCGCCCCAGGGUGGGGGCAAGCCGCCCAGCUCCGCACAGACCGCAGAGAUCUUCCAGGCGCUACAGCAGGAGUGCAUGAGGCAACUGCAGGCUCCGGCCGGCUCCCCGGCCCCCUCUCCCAGCCCGGGGGGUGACGACAAGCCCCAGGUGCCUCCUCGGGUACCCAUCCCCCCUCGGCCCACGCGCCCACACGUCCAGCUGUCUCCAGCCCCCCCGGGCGAGGAGGAGACCAGCCAGUGGCCUGGACCUGCUUCCCCUCCCCGGGUGCCUCCGCGGGAGCCCCUGUCCCCUCAAGGCUCGAGGACACCCAGCCCCCUGGUACCACCUGGCAGCUCCCCGCUGCCACCCCGGCUCUCAAGCUCACCUGGGAAGACCAUGCCCACCACCCAGAGCUUUGCCUCAGACCCCAAGUACGCCACCCCCCAGGUGAUCCAGGCCCCUGGCCCGCGGGCUGGUCCCUGCAUCCUGCCCAUCGUCCGGGAUGGCAAGAAGGUCAGCAGCACCCACUAUUACUUGCUGCCCGAGCGACCAUCCUACCUGGAGCGCUACCAGCGCUUCCUGCGUGAGGCCCAGAGCCCCGAGGAGCCUACCCCCCUGCCUGUGCCUCUGCUGCUGCCCCCACCCAGCACCCCAGCCCCCGCCGCCCCCACGGCCACCGUGCGGCCGAUGCCCCAGGCUGCCUUGGACCCCAAGGCCAACUUCUCCACCAACAACAGCAACCCAGGGGCCCGGCCACCACCCCCGAGGGCCACUGCUCGGCUGCCACAGAGGGGCUGCCCUGGCGAUGGGCCAGAGGCGGGCCGGCCAGCAGACAAGAUCCAGAUGCUGCAGGCCAUGGUGCAUGGGGUGACCACAGAGGAGUGCCAGGCGGCCCUGCAGUGCCACGGCUGGAGCGUGCAGAGGGCUGCCCAGUAUCUGAAGGUGGAGCAGCUCUUCGGGCUGGGUCUGCGGCCCAGAGGGGAGUGCCACAAAGUGCUGGAGAUGUUCGACUGGAACCUGGAGCAGGCCGGCUGCCACCUUCUGGGCUCCUGGGGCCCUGCCCACCACAAGCGCUGAGAUGCGUCUGGAGAGCCAGAGGGCCUGCCUGAAGGAAUCACCUGAGCCUGUCCGUCCACCAGGAGUGGGGAGAUGCCCCCAUCCAGUCCUGGAGGACCCGCUGCUCCUGCUGCUCCCGGGGAUGGAGCAAGGCCAAGGCUGCGGGAGGCUGGGAGCCCUGCCCUGCCCAUCCCUCCUGCACCAGCGCUGUCCCUGCACACUUUGGUUCAGUCCCGGUGCCCCUGCCAAGAUGUGGAAGGGGCCGGGUGAAGACAGGCUUGAGGGCUGCCCCAGCAGGCUCUGGGUAUGACCUGCCUCUGGCCCUGGUCCUGGGCGGGGCCUGUGGGUGGAGUAGUACCCCCAGGCCCUGCCCUGGGUGACAGACUGGGAGGAAACCAGGCUGGACCUGGGCAGGCGGGAUGUGUUGGCCACAGGGAGAGGCGGACCGGCACCCGGUGGGACCUCCUAGGACUGGGCCUUCUUCCAGGGGGCCCCUGGCAGCAGCUGGGGUGUCGGGCAGAAUGUGACUUGUGGCCUUACCAUGGACUUGAAUGGGACUUGGCUGGCCUCAGGAUCUUGUGCCUGGAAAUAGCCUGAGGUGGCUCAGGAAGCGGAGAAAGGGUGCCAGACCAUUCUCUGGCGGGGACCAGGGCCCAAGGCCCCAGGGCUGGAAGGAGACCAAGGGGCAGCCGCCCUGGAGGGACAUCAGUGCUUCCUCUUCCACCCAAUUCCCCCACGCGGUUCCAUGUUUUCCCACCAGCCUGUUGGCGAAGUUGCUGCUCCGGCAUUCAGUACCUGCUUCUUCCAGAGAAAUAAAGUUAGUUUCUAUUUUAUGUUA